AGUGGUAGCGGUUAUUCGGCGGCCCGCGGCGGACCAUGGCCCUGGCCCUGGCCCGGCGUCGCUGGGCUUUCCUCACGGCGUCCCCGAGCAGCGUCGCAGAGCGGGCCGACUUCCGGGAAGGAACUGACCAGCGACUGAGCGGCGGCCGGCGCGCUUAGCGCCCUGAACAUGCGGCAGUCCCUGCGGGCGACCCCGGGCUCCGGACAGGCGGCGGCGGAGGCGGCGGCUCGGGAGGGAAGGAGGCGGCGGCGCCGGCGGAGGUGGCGGCGGAGACGGCCGGCGCCCGGCGCGGAGCCCUAGGGAGGCAGUUCAGCGCGGCCUCGGGCCUCGUCGAGAAGGAUGCUGUCCCGAAAGAAAACCAAAAACGAAGUGUCCAAGCCGGCCGAGGUGCAGGGGAAGUACGUGAAGAAGGAGACGUCGCCUCUGCUUCGGAAUGCGUCGAGAUGUGCGUCAUGUUUGCAAACAUUGCGGGUGUCUCUCGACUGUGCUGCAAGUUGUGCGAACUCUGGGGCAGAAUUCCUUAGUCCUGCUGCCGGAUGCAGACUUGAGAAGAUCUUAUGCCUUCAUUCAUCCGGCAUGGUCCAACAAUUCCAAGACGAACUGAUAUCUGUCUUCCAGAUUCAAGCCCUAAUGCCUUUUCAACUUCUGGAGAUGUAGUUUCAAGAAACCAGAGUUUCCUUAGAACUCCAAUUCAAAGAACACCUCAUGAAAUAAUGAGAAGAGAAAGCAACAGAUUAUCUGCACCUUCUUAUCUUGCCAGAAGUCUAGCAGAUGUCCCUAGAGAGUAUGGUUCUUCUCAGUCAUUUGUAACGGAAGUUAGUUUUGCUGUUGAAAAUGGAGACUCUGGUUCCCGAUAUUAUUAUUCAGACAAUUUUUUUGAUGGUCAGAGAAAGCGGCCACUUGGAGAUCGUGCACAUGAAGACUACAGAUAUUAUGAAUACAACCAUGAUCUCUUCCAAAGAAUGCCACAGAAUCAGGGGAGGCAUGCUUCAGGUAUUGGGAGAGUUGCUGCUACAUCUUUAGGAAAUUUGACUAACCAUGGUUCUGAAGAUUUACCCCUUCCUCCUGGCUGGUCUGUGGACUGGACAAUGAGAGGGAGAAAAUAUUAUAUAGAUCAUAACACAAAUACAACUCACUGGAGCCAUCCUCUUGAGCGAGAAGGACUUCCUCCUGGAUGGGAACGAGUUGAGUCAUCCGAAUUUGGAACCUAUUAUGUAGAUCACACAAAUAAGAAGGCCCAAUACAGGCAUCCCUGUGCUCCUAGUGUACCUCGGUAUGAUCAACCACCUCCUGUCACAUACCAGCCACAGCAAACUGAAAGAAAUCAGUCCCUUCUGGUACCUGCAAAUCCAUAUCAUACUGCAGAAAUUCCUGACUGGCUUCAGGUUUACGCACGAGCCCCUGUGAAAUAUGACCACAUUCUGAAGUGGGAACUCUUCCAGCUGGCUGACCUGGAUACAUACCAGGGAAUGCUAAAGUUGCUCUUCAUGAAAGAAUUGGAGCAGAUUGUUAAAAUGUAUGAAGCAUACAGACAAGCCCUUCUUACAGAGUUGGAAAACCGAAAGCAGAGACAGCAGUGGUAUGCCCAACAACAUGGAAAAAAUUUUUGAGCUGAUUUUUUAAAAAUUUAAGUUUUGUAAGAGCUUUAAAAUAUUUUCACAGAUAAAAAAUUGCAAACAAGUACUCUGGUUAAUAAAUGCUGCUUCCUUUGUGGAAAUUAUAAAAUUCUAACUUUACAUGUAUUUUGUUAUUAGAAAUUUUCUUUUAUUGAAUGAGAAAAAUUAGUCUAUCAUUUUAAGAGCCAAUAUGGCAAACACUUUCAAAUACUGUAUAUUAGGAAACUGUUUUGGUAUUCUUGAUGGAAAAAAACGCAGCGGAAAUGUCAUUAUGAACAGAUGUUAAAUAGGAAAUUAUUACUUGUUAACUUCUUACAGCAGUAGUACCUUCUUUAAAAAAAAAAAAGAAUCUGCGGUAUUUUUUUAAAAAAAAAGUUUACCGCUGUAGUGUGAAAUAUUGUCUGGAAAGGGAUGGUUUAAAUAUUACCAUGAUGUAGUUGAAAUAUAAAAUAGGAUUUGGAACCUUAUUGUGAUAAAUAUUUAUAUAUGAUGUAUGUUUGUCUCCCCUCUCCAAAGUAAGGAACCCAGCUGGGCGUGGUGGCUCACUCCUGUAAUCCCAGCAUUUUGGGAGGCCGAGGUGGGUGGACCGCUUGAGUCCACGAGUUUAAGACCAGCCUGGGCAACAUGGUGAAGCCCCAUCUCUACAAAAAAUACAAAAAAAUUAGCCGGGUAUGAUGGUGUGUGCCUCUAGUCCCAGCUACUUGGGAGGCUGAGGUCAGAGGAUGGCUUGAGCCCAAGAGGCAGAGGUUGCAGGGUCAAGAUCGCACCACUUGCACUGCAGCCUGAGAGAGAGAGAGCCAGACCUUGUCUCAAAAAAUAAAAAAUAAAAAAAUAAAAACAAAAUAAGGAAUCCUUUUAAAGCAUGUUGAGAAAGUAUUUUUUGGUAUGAAUGGGUGACGGGCCUUUUAAUCUUUCAGGAAUACAUAUAAGCAGGAAUACUUAGCCUGUAUUGGGAAGGUGCGUGAAACUCAAAGUUGCUAACAUCAUCUUCCUUAUUUUCAGCCAGUGCUGUUACUGCAUUUAGCAUGGCUCUGACGAGGCAGUGGAGAGUUCCUGACAGCAUAGCAUACUGCCUUCUGACAGACUGGGUUAAGCUACCAAAAAUGACAACCAGGGAUUCAAAAAAAAUUUUUGGUCAUUAAAUCGAAUGUAUAUUAUUACUUUUUAAUUUUCUAAGUAUUUAUCACAGGACUUUAACACCAUAUAUUUCCCUCCCAGUUUUUCUCCCCUUUUGGUUUAAUAGUUAAAACAUUUUUCAUAAUUAGUGCUGUACAUUUGAUUGCAAACAAAUUGGUGAUACUUCUAAACUAUAACUAUAAAUCUCUAGAAUUCUGUGAAUUUCAACAUUAUUUGAAGUAGUUCUUCAGUUAUAUUUACAUGUGUUGUAAAUAUGUAAAUAUACUUUUAGCUUAGGAAGUCUUCCAGAAUACAAACUACUCCCAGUUAGAUAUCAGUGAGUUUGAAUAACUGAAGAAAUGUUGACAAUGUUAAGUGUUUGAUUUUAUAUAACAAGCUUAUUAAAUAUAUUUUUGUGGAAACUAAGCGCGUGGUUUUUGAGUCCAUGUUUUAGACAUAGUGCUGUAUUUCAUUUUUCUGU